AAUGUUGGAAGUCUCUUAGUCCUAUAAGAGUGUGUAGCAGUUUGUCCCUGAGCUCUAGCUUCUUUAAAUGAAGCUGAGUCUCUGGGCAACAUCUUUAGGGAGAGAGGUACAAAAGGUUCCUGGACCUUCUCAACACAGGGAGCCUGCAUAAUGAUGCAAGAGCAGCAACCUCAAAGUACAGAGAAAAGAGGCUGGUUGUCCCUGAGACUCUGGUCUGUGGCUGGGAUUUCCAUUGCACUCCUCAGUGCUUGCUUCAUUGUGAGCUGUGUAGUAACUUACCAUUUUACAUAUGGUGAAACUGGCAAAAGGCUGUCUGAACUACACUCAUAUCAUUCAAGUCUCACCUGCUUCAGUGAAGGGACAAAGGUGCCAGCCUGGGGAUGUUGCCCAGCUUCUUGGAAGUCAUUUGGUUCCAGUUGCUACUUCAUUUCCAGUGAAGAGAAGGUUUGGUCUAAGAGUGAGCAGAACUGUGUUGAGAUGGGAGCACAUUUGGUUGUGUUCAACACAGAAGCAGAGCAGAAUUUCAUUGUCCAGCAGCUGAAUGAGUCAUUUUCUUAUUUUCUGGGGCUUUCAGACCCACAAGGUAAUAAUAAUUGGCAAUGGAUUGAUAAGACACCUUAUGAGAAAAAUGUCAGAUUUUGGCACCUAGGUGAGCCCAAUCAUUCUGCAGAGCAAUGUGCUUCAAUAGUCUUCUGGAAACCUACAGGAUGGGGCUGGAAUGAUGUUAUCUGUGAAACUAGAAGGAAUUCAAUAUGUGAGAUGAAUAAGAUUUACCUAUGAGUAGAAGCUUAAUUGGAAAGAAGAGAAGAAUUACUGACGUAAUUUUUUCCCUGACGUCUUUAAAAUUGAACCCUAUCAUGAAAUGAUAAUUUCUUCCUGAAUUUACACAUAAUCCUUAUGUUAUAGAGGUUCACAGAAAUGGAAAGAUACCUGUUUCCCUUUAAUCAAUCUUCUCGUUUCCUCUUUUCCAUUAAUGAUAGAAUGCACCCUUCCUCUCUUUGUUCCAUUCUUUCACUUGUUAUUCAUUUUUUUCUUUCUUCACACUUCAUUACACAAAUAUUUAUUGUUUCAGAGACUGUACUAUUUUGUUUGUUAGAAGAUUUAUAAGGCAGUAUCUUUUGAAAAUUAUGACUUUCCUUCCUCAAUAUACCAUAAAGAAAUCUUUUUGGUCAAGAUGGUAGUUGGAACUACAAUCAUCUGAAGGCCUGACAAGAGUUGAAAGACAUGUUUUCUAGAUGGCUCACUCACAUGGCUGGCAACUUGGUGUUGGCUAUUAAUGUAACCUGGAAAUAAAUUUUAUUCUGCAGUUAGGGAUUUGGCAUUUUAUAUAUGUUGAUUCAAUCAAGUUUGGCAAGCAGGGUGUUCGAUACUGCUAUAUCCUGUAUUCUUGGUUUAUUUGUUUUAUUUCUGAGAAAUAUGUGUUAAGAUCUCUCGCUGAUUGGGAAUUUGUCUAUUUCUCAUUUAAAUUUUGUCAAAUCUUUCUUUGCUUGCAAGCAUUUCUUGUUACCCAAAUCUAAUCUAUUCCUGAAAAUAUGAUGGUUAGCAAAGUUUGAGAUAACUAGAGCCUGUAAUCCAUCAUUUUAAAUGGCAAUGAUAAUGACAGUUUAUUUUUAUGUUAUAUAAAAACCUCAACAAAUUUUCCAAAC